ACUCCACAGCUUUGCUCCCAGCCUGUCCACCUCACCCUCGGUCAACUUCCCCUGAGCCUGCUGCUGUCUCUUGAGCCCACUGUGAGAUCCAGAUAGAUACCCACUGAGGAGGAAGCAGGAUGGAGACAUGGGAUCAGGCGUUGCUUUCUUACUCUCUUGGAAGUUUAGGAUAUUUCACAGUUCUGAAUGUUAGCCACUGAAAAUGCCAGUAGAUGAUGAAGCCUCUGAAGAUGACACGGAUUCAUUUUUCUCAAACAGCCCAAGAACCUUUAUUUUCCAAUAAGAGAAUAUAACAAUUUCUGUACACUAUGGAAGAGUUUGACUUGGUGAAAACCUUACACAAAACUUCAUCUUCUGUAGGAUCUGAUGAAAAUUCUCUUCAUUCUCUUGGACUGAACUUAAAUACUGAUAGAAGUAGUCCCCACCUUAGUACAAAUGGGGUAUCCUCUUUCUCAGGGAAGACCAGACCAUCUGUAAUUCAAGGUACAGUUGAAGUCCUAACUUCUUUAAUGCAAGAGCUACAAAACAGUGGAAAGACUGAUUCGGAACUUUGGAAAAACUGUGAGACCAGGUGGUUACAGCUAUUCAAUUUGGUGGAAAAACAAUGCCAAGAACAGAUAGUUGCCCAGCAGGAGCAGUUCCACAACCAAAUUCAACAUAUACAGGAGGAGAUAAAAAAUUUAGUCAAAUUACAGACUAGUAGUGCUUCCUUAGCUUCCUGUGAAGGAAAUUCUUCAAACAAACAAGUAUCUUCGGAAAGUCAAAUGGGUUUUUUUUCUCUAAGCAGUGAGAGAAAUGAAUCUGUUAUCCAUUAUCCUGAAUCCACAGAACCUGAAAUACAGCAAGAAAUGUCCACGUCACAACCAGACUGCAAUGUGGAUAGUUGCUCAGUAAGCAGUGGAUAUGGCACCUUUUGUAUCUCAGAAUUAAAUCUGUACAAAUCUAAAGACCCUAAGGAGUUCAUGGAGCACAUAGAUGUUCCCAAAGGACAGUAUGUAGCACCUGCGGUGCCGGCUGAGUCACUUGUAGAUGGUGUGAAAAAUGAGAAUUUUUAUAUACAGACUCCUGAAGAGUGUCAUGUGUCUUUAAAGGAAGAUGUAUCCAUUUCUCCUGGUGAAUUUGAACAUAAUUUUCUUGGUGAAAAUAAGGUUUCUGAAGUAUACAGUGGGAAAACAAAUAGUAAUGCUAUAACAUCAUGGGCACAAAAACUGAAGCAGAACCAACCAAAGAGAGCACAUGUAGAAGAUGGAGGUUCAAGAUCUAAACAAGGAAAUGAGCAAAGUAAGAAGACACCAAUUGAGAAAUCUGAUUUUGCUGCUGCUACACAUCCUCGUGCUUUUUACCUCAGUAAACCAGAUGAAACUCCAAAUGCUUGGAUGUCUGAUUCAGGAACAGGAUUGACUUACUGGAAACUAGAGGAAAAGGAUAUGCACCACUCUUUGCCUGAAACUUUAGAGAAGACGUUCAUAUCAUUGUCUUCCACAGAUGUGUCACCAAACCAGUCUAAUACUAGUAAUGAGAUGAAGCUACCGUCACUGAAGGAUAUUUAUUAUAAAAAACAAAGGGAAAACAAGCAGUUACCUGAGAGGAAUCUCACUUCUGCUUCCAACCCAAAUCAUCCACCAGAGGUCCUGACUCUAGAUCCUACGUUACACAUGAAGCCAAAGCAGCAGAUUUCAGGGAUUCAACCUCACGGCCUUCCGAAUGCCCUUGAUGACAGAAUAUCCUUUUCCCCGGACUCUGUUCUAGAGCCUAGUAUGUCUAGUCCCUCUGACAUAGACUCAUUUUCACAAGCAAGUAAUGUCACUUCUCAGUUACCUGGAUUUCCAAAAUAUCCCUCACACACAAAAGCUUCUCCGGUGGACUCUUGGAAAAAUCAGACAUUCCAAAACGAAAGUAGGACCAGUUCCACGUUUCCGUCAGUAUAUACCAUUACUAGUAAUGAUAUCUCGGUCAACACUGUAGAUGAAGAAAACACUGUCAUGGUUGCUUCGGCCUCAGUCAGUCAGUCCCAGCUUCCAGGUACAGCCAACAGUGUCCCAGAAUGCAUUUCAUUGACUUCCUUGGAAGAUCCUGUGAUAUUGUCUAAGAUUAGGCAGAAUCUGAAGGAAAAGCAUGCUCGACACAUAGCAGAUCUUCGAGCUUAUUAUGAAUCAGAAAUAAAUAGUUUGAAACAGAAGCUGGAGGCAAAAGAAAUCUCUGGAGUUGAAGAUUGGAAGAUAACCAAUCAAAUUCUUGUAGACAGAUGUGGCCAAUUAGAUAGUGCUUUGCAUGAAGCUACUAGUCGCGUGAGAACACUUGAAAAUAAGAAUAACUUACUGGAAAUUGAAGUGAAUGAUUUGAGAGAACGCUUCAGUGCAGCCAGCAGUGCUUCCAAAAUUUUGCAGGAACGAAUUGAAGAAAUGAGAACAAGCAGUAAAGAAAAAGACAAUACCAUCAUUCGACUAAAAUCUAGACUGCAAGAUUUAGAAGAAGCAUUUGAGAAUGCUUACAAACUCUCAGAUGAUAAAGAAGCUCAACUAAAACAAGAGAACAAAAUGUUUCAAGAUCUUUUAGGAGAGUAUGAGUCCCUUGGAAAAGAACACAGGAGAGUAAAGGAUGCAUUAAAUACAACUGAGAACAAAUUGCUUGAUGCAUAUACUCAGAUUUCUGAUUUGAAAAGAAUGAUUUCAAAACUUGAAGCUCAGGUCAAGCAAGUAGAACAUGAAAAUAUGUUAAGCCUUCGUCAUAAUUCUAGAAUUCACGUGAGACCCUCGCGUGCCAACACACUAGCAACUUCAGACGUCAGCAGGCGGAAAUGGCUGAUUCCAGGUGCAGAGUAUUCCAUCUUUACUGGCCAGCCUCUGGACACCCAGGACAGUAACGUGGAUAACCAGCUGGAGGAAACCUGUAGCCUAGGGCACCGUUCACCUCUGGAAAAGGAUUCUUCACCUGGAAGUUCAUCAACAAGCUUGUUGAUAAAAAAGCAAAGAGAGACUUCAGACACGCCGAUCAUGAGAGCUUUAAAAGAACUUGAUGAGGGAAAAAUAUUUAAAAAUUGGGGGACACAGACAGAGAAAGAGGACACCUCAAAUAUAAAUCCUCGGCAAACUGAAACUUCAGUUAAUGCAAGUCGUUCUCCAGAAAAGUGUGCCCAACAGAGACAAAAGAGACUUAAUUCGGCCUCACAGAGAUCAUCAUCUUUACCACCUUCAAAUCGUAAAUCAAGUACUCCAACAAAAAGAGAGAUUAUGCUAACACCAGUGACUGUGGCUUAUAGUCCAAAGCGAUCCCCUAAAGAAAACUUGUCCCCAGGAUUUAGUCAUCUGCUUAGCAAAAAUGAGAGCAGUCCAAUUCGAUUUGAUAUACUUUUGGAUGAUUUAGAUACUGUUCCUGUGUCUACAUUACAACGUACCAAUCCAAGAAAGCAACUCCAGUUUCUUCCUCUAGAUGACUCGGAAGAAAAAACUUAUUCUGAGAAAGCCACCGAUAACCAUGUUAAUCAUAGCUCUUGCCCUGAACCGGUGCCAAAUGGAGUGAAGAAAGUAUCUGUGAGAACAGCCUGGGAGAAGAAUAAAUCAGUUAGCUACGAACAGUGUAAGCCGGUUUCAGUCACUCCACAGGGGAAUGAUUUUGAAUAUACAGCAAAAAUUCGGACCCUAGCUGAAACAGAACGAUUUUUUGAUGAACUUACAAAAGAAAAGGACCAGAUUGAGGCAGCACUAAGCAGGAUGCCUUCUCCUGGAGGACGAAUCACUUUACAGACAAGAUUAAAUCAGGAAGCCUUGGAAGAUCGUUUGGAAAGGAUUAAUCGAGAACUGGGUUCAGUUCGCAUGACGCUAAAGAAAUUCCAUGUUUUGCGCACCUCUGCAAAUCUUUGAGAUUUGUAGCCAUUAAAUUUUGAGACAUUUUUGUUUGCACUAAUGUAUAAUUAUGCAGUCAGAAAAGGCAAACUAUUUUGUACUGUUUAUAAGCCUUCAAACAGUAGUUUUACAAUCAUGCUAUUCUUACACUUGCUAUUUUAUACUUCAAAUGGCCACAUAUUUUCAAGAUAUUUUUGUUAUGCUCAGGAAUCUCUUGUAUAUUUUACUAUUUAAAAAGCAUUAUUUUUAAAUAGUAUCUGUCUCCAAUUUAUAUCAAGAAUAAGGAAAUAUAAACAGAGGAAGCAGCUUGUUUCUAAACAAAUAGUGUUAUCCUUUUACAAUUAACUGCACAUCAAUUUUAUAGACUUGUUCUACAUUGUAAAUACAAUUCAGUUUUUAAAAAAUAAAGCUUAAUAGCUUCCAUAAUGAUAGACUAGUACAUGCUGAAUACAUAAACAAUUACAGUGUACCUUGGAUUUCAGUUGUGUUGAGGUUUUUAAAAAAUGAUAAUGCAAUUCGUAUUUGAAACGUGUCUUAGAGUGAAUAUCAGAAUAGUAAUAAUGGACUCUUGGAAAGCUUUGAAAACUACAUGAAUAUAACUCAUUUUCUUUAAACUUUAUUGUCUGUAAGAGAAAAAAGAGAGAUUGUAAUUCUCUAAUUUUAUCUUUUCUAAAAAAGUUAAACAAUUGGAGAGCCCUCUCUGGAGGGCUCUCAGAGUAGCUCUCUGCCCAUUGUUCUGAAUUAACUUGUGUCCCACCCUGGACAAUAAAUGGACAGAUAAACCCUUUGAAAUACAAGCCACCACCCCGUGAGGGAUUAAGAGGGCAGCCUGGUUUUCUUAGUGUGCAUGGCUUCAGCUGUCCGUCAUAGUUGUCAUCUGGAUAUGUUCACCCCUUUCCACUCCUUCACCCUGGCCAAAAGGAAAAUAUUUCCACUGUAGGUGCUGUAAGAACACUAGACUUUAGAUCAUCACAAUCUACUGUAUUUGUUAAUGGACAGGGAGUGUGUCCGGAUGGAGCCUGGUGCCUUCCCCUCGGCCUUGCAGAGGGCUCCAGCCCACUGCCUCUGUGGUAGCCGCUGGCUCUCAGAAGUAGCACGUGGGCAGGAGUCUCUCCUCUGAUCCAGGAGCAUUGGCAGGUUUGUGUUGGGACUGCUGGUUAAGUUGGAGCUGUGUAACUACUUAGUUUUUGGUAGCCAAUCAGAACGCAGUGCCCCACAUAUUCCAGCUCGGUACAUGUUGAUAAACAGACUCAUCCAAACUUUCAAAAUGGAUUCGUACUAAACAUGCUCAGGUUUUAAAUUUUGGUUUGCUUUUGAGCUUUUCCUCUUUAUGUGGCUCUUAAUAAUAAGUAGUUAGAAUGAACCAAGCCAUCCCAGUUAUUCCAAGCAGGCUCUCAAAUGACCUUUGAGCACCCUUCACCUGGCUGGUCCCCAGGCCAGGGGUCCACAGCCCUGCUCCCUUCUCAGCAAGGAGGGUGGCCUGUCUGACAGUGCAGUUGAACCUUUGCUCCCUACUCUGCAACUUUUGAAGACUUCAGGCUAAUCAAAAUUACUUAUAAUUAGAAUCAAGUGCCUUUAUUCUUGUUUUUUAUUUUUAUUUUAUUUUAUUUAUUUAUUUUUUUAGAUGGAGUUUUGCCCUUGUUGCCCAGGCUGGAGUGCAAUGGCAUGAUCUCAGCUCACUGCAACCUCUGCCUCCCGGGUUCAAGCGAUUCUCCUGCCUCAGCCUGCUGGGUAGCUGGGAUUACAGGCAUCUGCCACCACGCCCGGCUAAUUUUGUCUGUGAAGAGGGAUACCAAGGAAAGUUCUUUCUGCUGUCUUUCUCUUCGGUAAUGCUUAUCUUAUGAACACUCAACUGAAAAAACACUCCACCUAAAAGCAGGAAAGAUGGCAAUUCUAAAUAGCAGCUAUUAUCCCCGGGUAUAAACUAUUUUUGUUGUUGGCUUGGGGCUUUGCUGCAGGUAUUAAUAGUUUAAAAAGAAAAAAAAAAAAAAAACCCUAAGCAAAUCUGCCACCUCUGGGAAGUGCCUUUUAAAAUGCAAAUAGAAAGUGAACUCUCCCCUGAUGCCUGGAUCUGCCCCCUUCCUUUCCCUUGCUAAGCCUCUGUUUGCAGGAGCUACUCCUGAGGUAUGGAAAUGGUCUUUGCAACUGAAGGACUUUUCCAACUGAAGCAACAGAUGUAGCUAAAGUGGCCGUGCUAGGGUUGUGCAGAGCUGGGCUCAGGGGACAAGAAAGGAGAGACUUGGAGCCAGAGAGACCUGGGUCACAUCCUGGCACAGGCCUGCCUUUCUCAGCUAUAAGAUGAAAUAAGAAAACUCCUUUCAUUAAGGGAGAUUUUGUAAAGUGCCUGGUGCUUAGUAAGUGCUCAAGAAAUAUUAUAUUUCAGAUUCAUUGAGUUAAGUAGGUUUUUGAGGUAGCAUCCUUUUUUUUUUUUUUUUUUUUUUUUGAGAUGGAGUCUCUAGUUCUGUUGCCCAGGCUGGAGUGCAGUGGUGUGAUACUGGCUCACUGCAACCUGUCUCCUGGGUUCAAGCUAUUCUCCUGCCUCAGCCUCCCGUGUAGGUGGGAUUACAGGUGCAUACCACGCCUGGUUAAUUUUUGUAUUUUCGGUAGAGACGGGGUUCUCACCAUGUUGGCCAUCCUGGUCUUGAACUUCUGACCCCAAAUGAUCUGCCUGCCUUGGCCUCCCAUAGUGUUGGGAUUACAGGCGUGAGCCACUGCGCCCAGCCUUGAGGUAGCAUACUUUCUGAAAUAAAAAAGUAGAUUAUGUCCGAAGCAGUUGACCUAAAAACUGCCUUGGACUGACAUUUGUUAGGUGGUCUAAGAUGUUCUCUUCACGCUUUGCAAAAAAAUGAGCUUUUUUGGAGUUUAAAUUAAGCAUCCCUCUGGUGUGUUUGGUUUUUUAGCCACCAAAAAUUUAACAAAUUUGAUAACCUGUCACGUGUAAGUUCAGAAAGCACUUUGGUCUUAAUUGGUGACUUGGGGGUUAUUUGGUAUAAAUAUAGGUUGUUUUUCUAAAAAUUAUUGCCAGUAUCCUCCAAAUAAUUGCCCCUUCAAAUGUUUCAUCUAAAGGUGACAGCUUGUGGGCAGAACCAUGCACAGGAAGUGCCUGCCAGUGGGUGUUAGGAGAUGUAGGUGGAGUCUGUGAUAGCCAACCAAAAGCUAUCCCCUUCUCGCCCAGAAAAGCCACGUGCUUUGCUGGACGCUACUUGAAAUCUGAACUCUGCACCUACAUAUGUAGUAAAAUUAGACACUUUUGUCACUUUAAUUUUUAGAUUAUCUCAAGUUUUCACUAGAUUUCAAUGUGCCACUUGUGCUAUGAGUCUUUAAGAAGCUUUAAAAAAUAAAUGCACACCUGUAGCCUUUUACCAUUCAGACAGGUAGAUUAUAUUUACCUGUCAUGAGGGACCAUGUAUGGUUGACAGUUGCAGGUUUGAUUAAAUCCACUAUAUUGCACAAAUUUUGCUGGAAAUAAUUUCCUGCCCUGCCAAGAGCUCUAUGGUAGUUUGAUAAUAAACUACUACCCCAGUAUUCUUAGGAACUGUGUUACUAAGUCUUUUCUGCCUGAUUUGUACUUUAUUUCCAUAGACCCCUCAGAUAUGUGAGGAAUCAAGCCAUAAAUGUGCAUUUGCUGGACAUUAUGUACCAUGUCAUCUCUAUGACUACAGAUUUCAAGGAUAAUUUUUACAUCUAACAAUUUCACUGUAACAGUGACCGAUAAUGUGAGAAAUGUGCUUUUUACAGUGCUGCUGGUGGGUAGACAAGUGCUUGCUGCAGUUGUUUCUGAAUCUAGCCAGAUGCUGGAGUCGUGAAGCUGUAAGCUCCGCGGGAGCAGGGACCAUCUCUCUUUCUUGCACUACAGGCACUCAAUAAAUACUUGUGGCUGUGAA